AAGCCACUUUUUCCUCUCUCCAAUUUUGCAACGACGGGCGCGGAGGAGGAGGUUCCCGGAAGCCACGCGCAGCUGGAGCAGCGGCGACCGCAGCUGGAGGCCCGGAGCGCCUGCGGGGCUGGCAGAGGCGAGGGAGGUUGCGGGUAGGAAGGGCGGACUGCGCGCGCCCCCUGCGUCCCGCGCACCUCGGGGCCGGUCCAUGCUCCCGACGGCUGCGGGCUUCAGCAUCUGGGGCCAGGUUGGGGCGGCGGGGUCCAGGGCGCAGGUGGUGCGGCCGAUGCGCCGGGCCGGAGGCUGAGGCCGCGCUGCGGGGCUGGGACAGCACUGGCAUCUCCAGAGCAGGCCCGGGGCAGCAAGGGAGGCGCCGCGAUGCCAGACGAAAAUAUCUUCCUGUUCGUGCCCAACCUCAUCGGUUAUGCCCGGAUUGUCUUCGCCAUCAUUUCUUUCUACUUCAUGCCCUGCUGCCCCCUCACGGCCUCCUCCUUCUACCUGCUCAGCGGCCUGCUGGACGCUUUCGAUGGACACGCUGCUCGCGCUCUUAAUCAAGGAACCCGGUUUGGGGCCAUGCUGGACAUGCUGACGGACCGCUGCUCCACCAUGUGCCUGUUGGUCAACCUGGCCCUGCUGUACCCUGGAGCCACGCUGUUCUUCCAAAUCAGCAUGAGUUUGGAUGUGGCCAGUCACUGGCUGCACCUCCACAGUUCUGUGGUCCGAGGCAGUGAGAGUCACAAGAUGAUCGACUUGUCCGGGAAUCCGGUGCUUCGGAUCUACUACACCUCGAGGCCUGCUCUGUUCACCUUGUGUGCUGGGAAUGAGCUCUUCUACUGCCUCCUCUACCUGUUCCAUUUCUCUGAGGGACCUUUAGUUGGCUCUGUGGGACUGUUCCGGAUGGGCCUCUGGGUCACUGCCCCCAUCGCCUUGCUGAAGUCGCUCAUCAGCGUCAUCCACCUGAUCACGGCCGCCCGCAACAUGGCUGCCCUGGACGCAGCAGACCGCGCCAAGAAGAAGUGACGCUGGAGCCCCGGGUCCUGGCUGCCCACCUGCCCUGGGAGUCUUGCUGUGCCACACAGCUCCCCACCCCCUGCUAGGAGGUCCCAGUCUCACGCCUUCCUCAUGUGUUGUUCUACCUGCUGGGAUGGGGGUCAGCCUCUCUUUGGUGACGUCACGUUCUCUGGGAUCCUGAGGACCCGGGCCUCAAAUCAGGGAGGAUACGCGGGAGGCCCCCUCCAUCCAGGCGGUGCUCCUGGGGUGCCGGGACCGGGCAGUGUCACACCCUGCCUGCUCAGUCCUGGGGUCCGAGAUGCUAGGGACGCUUGAGUGAGGGAGGUGGUGUGAGGGCCAGGUUUCCUGAAAGGCGGGAGUCAGACCUCCGCCCCCAGCCAGAGCAAGCUUGGGGCACCAUGCCCAGGAGGGAAGAAGCCAUCCACAGCCUUCCCUGUCACCGGCUCCUCUGUCCUGCCUACCCUGGUCCUGGCGGGACUUCACUAUUUGACUUGGUUUCCUUUCAGAUAUUCUUGGCUCAGGGCCUGGGUUGAGGGAGCUUAGGGAAGGACGUCCGUCUGGGUGCUUUUCCUCCAGUUUGCUGGCUGGCUUCUCCGUCUACCCACAGUGACCUCACAGAGAGGCCCUCCUGCCACCCAUGCUCAUGUGGUGUCCCCACCGCCCACUUGUUUGAUGUCACUGACUGUCUACAUGUAUUUAUAUUCUUGAUAUUUUCUACCCUCACUAGAAUGUAAACUCCAUGAAGGCACAGACUUUUCUUGUUCUCUUCUCUAUCCCUAGAGUAAGACCAACUUGAACCUGGCAUAUAGUAGCUGCUUAAUAAAUACUCGUCUGUCAAUGA